AUGAACGAAAAUCUGUUCGCUUCAUUCAUUGCCCCCACAAUCCUAGGCCUACCCGCCGCAGUACUGAUCAUUCUAUUUCCCCCUCUAUUGAUCCCCACCUCCAAAUAUCUCAUCAACAACCGACUAAUCACCACCCAACAAUGACUAAUCAAACUAACCUCAAAACAAAUGAUAACCAUACACAACACUAAAGGACGAACCUGAUCUCUUAUACUAGUAUCCUUAAUCAUUUUUAUUGCCACAACUAACCUCCUCGGACUCCUGCCUCACUCAUUUACACCAACCACCCAACUAUCUAUAAACCUAGCCAUGGCCAUCCCCUUAUGAGCGGGCACAGUGAUUAUAGGCUUUCGCUCUAAGAUUAAAAAUGCCCUAGCCCACUUCUUACCACAAGGCACACCUACACCCCUUAUCCCCAUACUAGUUAUUAUCGAAACCAUCAGCCUACUCAUUCAACCAAUAGCCCUGGCCGUACGCCUAACCGCUAACAUUACUGCAGGCCACCUACUCAUGCACCUAAUUGGAAGCGCCACCCUAGCAAUAUCAACCAUUAACCUUCCCUCUACACUUAUCAUCUUCACAAUUCUAAUUCUACUGACUAUCCUAGAAAUCGCUGUCGCCUUAAUCCAAGCCUACGUUUUCACACUUCUAGUAAGCCUCUACCUGCACGACAACACAUAA